AAAGUCCAUACUUUAUUUAUAUUUCCAUAGUUUUUGCAAAAUUUCCUUUUCCUGUUCCAGUAUUCUAUCAAGGGUACCACACUACAUUGAGUCGUUAUGUCUUUUUAGGUUCCUAUCGUUUGUGACAAUUUCUCAGACUUUCCUUGUUUUGAUGACCUUUGAGGAGAACUAGUCAGAUGUUUUGUAGAAUUUUCUUCAUUGGGAUUUGUCUGAUGUUUAUCUGAUGACUAGACUGCAGCUAUGGGUUUUGGGGAGGAAGACAACAGAGGUAAAGUGCCAUUUGUGCCGCAUCAUAUCCAAGGUACCUACUAGCGACGUGAUUUGACUGUUGGAGUUGACUUUCAUCACCUGGCUGAGGUCAUCACGUUUGUCAGUUUCUCCACUGUAAAGUUACUUCCCACCUGCCCCCGCCCCCGCCCCGCCACCCCAGCGCUUUCCAUAAAACACUCUUGGAAAGGGAGUCAUUAUGUGCACCUCGCACUUUCAAAAUGGGGAGUUACAGUUCCCCUCCUCAAGGACUGAGUUAUCUAGAUACAGAAUUUGGAAUUCUGCAUGGGAGAUUUCUCUUUUCUACCUGUUUGUUCAGUUAUUUUUAUCAGUAUGGACUCAUAGAUAUUUAUUUCAUACUUUUUGUUACAGUCCAAUAUUACCUUAUUUAUUUUGUCACUCAAAUUUUUCCAGCUUUGGCCAUUGGGAACUCUUUCAGUUAGCUCCUACCCCCACCAUUUGUGUGUGUGUGUGGUGUGUGUGUAGUGUGUGUGGUGUGUGUAGGUAGUGUAUGUGUGUGGUGUGUGUGUAGUAUGUGUAUUGUGUGUAUGGUGUGUGUGUAGUGCGUGUGGUGUGUGUGGUGCAUGUGGUAUGUGUGUGGUGUGUGUAGUGUGUGUGUAGAGUGUGUGUGUGGCAUGUGUGUGUAGUGUGUGUGGUGUGUGUAGUGUAUGUGUAGUGUGUGUAGAGUGUGUGUGGCAUGUGUGUGUGGUGUGUGGUGUGUGUGUGUGUGUAGCAUUUCUUUACUUUCUGGCACUAUCAGAUGCUCUGGGCUCAUCUUGUAGUGUUUCCUGCCCAAGUCCUAUAAACAGCAAUUUCUUCAAGGAGCCUUGGAUCCUUUUAUUGGAGAAUGGUAUUAGAAACCAAGAUUUCAGUGCUACGUGUGCUUGUUGCUAUGGAGUAUCAUUGCUUCUAGGCCCUCUCGCCUGACAGUAAGGAAAUAAAUGUGUGUAUACUAGCCCGUGUGUGUGUGUGUGUGUGUGUGUGUGUAUUAUAUAUAUAUAUAACUUUCUGUAUGUAAUCAUCUGCAUCUAUAUUAAGCUAAACAUGAGUUCAUUCUGGUAUCUCCAAUUCUAAUCUGUUGCCACAUGGAUCAUUCUAGCCUCCUCCUCAGGGGUCAUUUUUAUCAGAAGCAAUGUUGCUUAGUAACAUAGCAGACAUAUGUUUAUCUGUUUCCAGGAAACAGAGCUUCCAAAGGUCAAAUUCUCAUGCAAAAGAGGAAAAGGUUUUGUUAACCCUUUACUUACAUUCAUCAGUGAGGCUCUCCACUGCUCUGAGGAUAAAGAACAAAUUACUUGGCCUGUAAGGCUCUGCAGUGACCUGACCUGCUAAGCCCAGGCUCGUCUCCUACCAGGUUCCUUAUCAGGCCCUCCAUGACAACCAUACUGGUCUCCUGCAACUCUCAAACUCGUCACACACUUCCUUCUACCCCAAGGUCUUCGCCUAUGCUAGGCGCUCUGCUGGACUUCUCUUUCCUCCCCUCUUUAUCUGGUUGCCUUCUACUCAUCCUUCUAAUCUCAGCUCAGUCCACACUUUUACAGGAAGCCAUUCCUAUCCCCAAGACUAGGUUGGCACCCUUGUUUGAGGCUUGCACUCUAUACUUUUAUUUGGUAGCAUUUACUAUAACUGCAAUGUUACAUUUACUUAUCCUUUUCUCCCACUAGAAUACAAGCUUCCUGAGUGUAGGGAUGGAGUCUACCUAGCUAACUAGUAUAUAAUAUUUGCCCAUUUUCUCUGUUCUUUAUUCAGUGAGCACUUAUCCAGAGCUUCCUAGGUGUUAGCCCCUUUUCUAGUGUCUGGGGAUACUGCAGGGAGGGAAACAGGCAAAAACCCUCUUCUUUUGGCACUUAUUUUUUAGGGGAGGUGGCAAUAAGCAAACAGAAACUAAUGUCAGUUGGUAAGUGCUAUAGAGAAAAAUUCAGAGUGAGGGAGUAAAGAGUGCUGGGGCACUGCUAUUUUUGAAAGGAUGGCCUGGAAUGGCGUCUCUGAGAAGGUGGCAUUUGAGCAAAGACUUGAAGGAAGUGAGGGAAGGGGGUGAGUGCGGGAAAUAUCAGAAAGAAAAACGUCCCAGGCAGAAGGAACAGCCAGCGCAAAGGCUGAGGUAGGACAGCGCAUGACUGAGGGAAGGAACAGUGAGUGCUUUAAAGGCGGUAUCUCAUCCCAUUCCCAUAACACUUCCUACAUCCGUUUCACAGAGGAGGAAACCGAGCUCCAGGAGGGCAGUCCUUUACACCAGGGCACCCAGCUGUGGGGGUGGAGCUGGGAUUUGAACAGGAGUGUGGUGCCAGGGCUAGCAUCCCUUUGAAGUCUCUAACAACGGGCCAGGCCUCUGCAAGGCUGGGAGGAAAUGGAGGCCUUCCCAGCCCUGGUGGACCUGCCUAGGGCUAGGCUAUGCUGGCCUUGAAGGCACAGGCAUCCAUCAUCCAGGGUGACUUCCAGUCUCCUGGUUGGGGAGGGCUGCACAGAACUUUGGAGGAGGGCAGGUCAGGCUCCGCUCAUGAGGUGGCCGAGGAGCAGGACAUGGCACACUCAUUCGCCUGUCCUUCCACAUGGCCAACUUCUGCUGGCCUUCCCAGAGCCCUCAAAGCCUGCACAUUCACAAUCCUCAUGGACAGAAGUGGAUACAGGCUCAGAGGCCAGAGGAGCUGCCAAUCCGAUGGAGGAGGCUGACCCUUAAACAAAAUCACGACCGUCAGAGACAAGAGCAAACAGUGCGGGCAAAAGGAGAGCCCAGAUGGAGGGGCCCGUGGGCUGCCAAGGGGCCAAGGGAUGAGCUGGGGCCCUCCUUCCCAAUGGCAUCUCCCCCUGGUCUGGAACUGAAGACACUGAGCAAUGGUCCCCAAGCCCCAAGGAGAUCAGCUCCCCUGGGCCCAGUGGCCCCAACCAGGGAGGGUGUGGAGAAUGCCUGCUUCUCCUCAGAGGAGCAUGAGACCCAUUUCCAGAACCCUGGGAACACGAGACUGGGCAGCUCACCCAGUCCCCCUGGGGGUGUCUCCUCACUGCCCCGAUCCCAGCGGGAUGAUCUGUCCCUUCAUUCAGAGGAGGGGCCAGCCCUGGAGCCCGUGAGCCGCCCGGUGGAUUAUGGCUUUGUUUCCGCCCUCGUUUUCCUGGUGAGUGGGAUUCUUCUGGUGGUGACAGCAUACGCCAUCCCCCGUGAGGCUCGAGUCAAUCCGGACACAGUGACAGCGCGGGAGAUGGAACGACUGGAGAUGUACUACGCCCGCCUAGGCUCCCACCUGGACAGGUGCAUCAUCGCAGGCCUCGGGCUGCUCACGGUGGGCGGCAUGCUCUUGUCGGUGCUGCUCAUGGUCUCCCUGUGCAAGGGCGAGCUGUACCGCCGGAGGACCUUCGUCCCCGGCAAGGGCUCCAGGAAGACCUACGGCUCCAUUAACCUGCGCAUGAGACAGCUCAAUGGGGAUGGGGGCCAGGCCCUGGUGGAGAAUGAAGUUGUCCAGGUCUCAGAGACUAGCCACACCCUCCAGAGGUCUUAAGAACUAGCCCACCUUAUCUGGCUGCUUUAGCUCCAGUGCUACAAGGUCCACCCCCUGCUCCCGCCCACCUGACCCCUGCCAAGGCCCUGGGGUUUUAAACUGAGCUCACAUAGGGCCUUGUGGAAGAAGUACUGGGUGCUGGAGGGAGAGCUCGGGGCCCAGCCCAUGCCCCACACGGGCAAGCAGCCCACUGAUCUGUUUUGUAGCUGAGGUUUUGCAUACGGUUUUGUUUGGAGGAUGGCUUCUGCUGCUAAAAAUACAAAAGUUUGGAAACCGCU